AGAUUAUUUUUGGCUCCGCAGCCGGGGCUGCUCGCUGCUUGUCGCGCGCUCACACACACACAGACACACACGCACACACACACAUGCACACAUUUUCUCGCGCUCUCUCCGGCUCUCCUUUGUUUAUUUUCUAAUCUAUAUUUUUACUGGAAGAUUUCCUCUUUAUUCUCUCCCGCCCUCCUACAAGCGCUCUUGCUGGCCGUCUGGGUGCACACACCGCUCCCUCGAUCACCCCAGCCCCCUUCCUGGUCUCCCGAGCGCGGGGUUUGAAGGUCACCUCCUUUCCAGUCCCCGUGCGAGCCGCGCUGCCGCCGCCUCCUCCAGCCAGAGUCGGUGGGACUGGCUGCGCUGCCCUGAAGUGGUUCUCCAAGCAGCGCGGAGGGUGGCGGACGGCGGACGGAGCCCAGGGGCCGCGUCGGGUGGGGAAACCCGAACUCGCGGAGGGGAAUCCCUCCCCCUCCGCCCCAGCCCCCCAGCAGCACCCGCGGUGGGGCGGGGGCGCUCUGCCAGCCCCGGGAACAGCAGAGGCGGCGGCACUGGCUGGACCCACGCGCGCGCCUCCGGGGCUGAAGAAGGAAGGAGUGAGCCGAGCCGAGCACCCCACAUCUGGAGGGGACAGCCAGCCGUGGGCCCCGCCCCGGCGUCCGGAGCAGGAGAACUCCGAGCUUCUUGCCCAGGCAGAGAGAGCAGGAGCGGACCGCGCGCCCGGGAUUGAGAGUCCUUGCGCUCCAGACCCCCACCCAGUGGCCGCCAGGGUCCCCGCCUGUCCGGACCCUCGCCGCGCCCAGGCAGGCGCGCCAGGGCGGGGCUGACCUGCCCGCGAAGUUGCGGACAGUGCGUGAGAAACCAGCACCCCCUUCCGCCGCCUCCAGCUUAUGGAAACUGGUCAAAGAACUCAUGCAAGUGGAACUUACAGCUUCCUUGAUCGGACUCAGCAUUCAGAUAUCAAAGCAGACUGCAAUACCUGCGUGGAAAUAGAAGACAGAAAGGUUUCAAGACAACAGAUGAAUUGUGAAAGAGAGCAGCUAAGGGGUAAUCAGGAAGCAGCCGCUGCCCCUGACACAAUGGCUCAGCCUUACGCUUCGGCCCAGUUUGCUCCCCCGCAGAACGGUAUCCCCGCGGAAUACACGGCCCCUCAUCCCCACCCCGCGCCAGAGUACACAGGCCAGACCACGGUUCCCGAGCACACAUUAAACCUGUACCCUCCCGCCCAGACGCACUCCGAGCAGAGCCCGGCGGACACGAGCGCUCAGACCGUCUCUGGCACCGCCACACAGACAGAUGACGCAGCACCGACGGAUGGCCAGCCCCAGACACAACCUUCUGAAAACACGGAAAACAAGUCUCAGCCCAAGCGGCUGCAUGUCUCCAAUAUCCCCUUCAGGUUCCGGGAUCCGGACCUCAGACAAAUGUUUGGUCAAUUUGGUAAAAUCUUAGAUGUUGAAAUUAUUUUUAAUGAGCGAGGCUCAAAGGUAAAUAAUGCCACAGCACGUGUAAUGACAAAUAAAAAGACCGUCAACCCUUAUACAAAUGGCUGGAAAUUGAAUCCAGUUGUGGGUGCAGUCUACAGUCCCGAAUUCUAUGCAGUGCCAGGCUUCCCGUAUCCAGCAGCCACCGCCGCGGCCGCCUACCGAGGGGCGCACCUGCGAGGCCGCGGUCGCACCGUGUACAACACCUUCAGGGCCGCGGCGCCCCCGCCCCCGAUCCCGGCCUACGGCGGUGUUGUUUACCAGGAUGGAUUUUAUGGUGCAGACAUUUAUGGUGGUUAUGCUGCAUACCGCUACGCCCAGCCUACCCCUGCCACUGCCGCUGCCUACAGUGACAGUUACGGACGAGUUUAUGCUGCCGACCCCUACCACCACGCACUUGCUCCAGCCCCCACCUACGGCGUUGGUGCCAUGCCCCAAGGUUCCAGCCCCAGCACAGACUUCAGAGGAGCUAAGCUGCACACUUCCAGGCCUCUGCUGUCAGGCAGCUGAGAAUCUGACUGCCUCUCCUCCCCUAUUACAAUUCAUGUUUAAAGUCAUAGUCGCCCAGGAAAGAAAAUAGAGAGGGGCACACUUUGUGUGUGUACCUAGUACAUAAGAAAGUAGAAGGAAUCAGCUGGGUUUGGGGGUUGCCUUUUGUUUUGGGGCAGGUCUGGGUUUUUGUUUUGGGAGGGGGUGGGGGGAGGGUAAAAAAUGGGAGGUAAGGGUGGGGUGAACUUGCCUGUACUUGUUCAAACUUCUAUGCACUGAAACUCUUGAGUACAGUAAGACGUGCCCAUCACGUGAGAGCAUAUGCAAUCAUUACAAAGCUUUGGCAUGCAGUUUUCUGCUUGGAUCAAGAAUAUCAGUCCUUACCCUAAAAAUGAAUCCCCAUAGGCAUUCAUUUGAAUUGCCAAUACUUUUAGAAAAAGGAAAUCGUUAAGUGCCACCUUGUAGCCAUUAAAACCAUGGCCGGACAGUUCACUGAAGCUCAGUCAUAGAAAUUCAGCCAUGAUUUGGAAGCAUUGUUUUGCACAAGCUUAAUUACAUCAAGCAAUUCAUCUGUACAACUCCACAACUCCCUUCUCAAGAUCAGAUUCCAUACAGCUUACAGAGCCAAGUUAAGUAAGAAGUAGGUUGAGAUUUUCAUCCCAAUUCUGCAUUCAACAACUCUGCUUCAACACCUAGUCCACAUGAGGAAUGUGUUGGAGAGUUGAAUUACAUUCAACAACUGGUCCAAAUUCAACCUCAAGUGCAGAUUAUUCUGUUAUAAAAAAAUGAGACAGUGAAAAUCCUUCCAUUGUCCAGCUUAUAAUAGAGUCCUUUUAGCUAAGAGGACUGGCUGACAGAAUUUGGUUUUGCAGGGAAUUUCUUUAGGAGGAGCUAUUGGGGAAGGUCAGGAAUGGCCCUAUCUUUAGUUCUCCAAGAAUGACCUGGGAUGGGUAGGGGGUGCCUCCAUUUCGGUUGGUUUUGAGUGUCUAUUUUUCACAUUAGUCUUUUUGAUGAUCCACAUGUUGCAAAAGGAAAAUGUAAAAAACACACCCCUCAAAUUGCUUUGUUUCAGAAUGCUUUUGCACCUUUGACUGAUGCCAAGACUAGGAGCCAUGCUGAUGAUGUGGGUCUCGUUCUUUCUUCAUUGCAGGCUAGUAUAUACCGAGGGGGAUACAACCGUUUUGCUCCAUACUAAAUGACAAAACCAUAAAAACCUUCCAAUGUGGGGAGAAAGGAAGCUUUCCGAGGCCUGAGUAUUGCAAUACAUGCAGUAGUACAUCAUUUUAGCAACUCUAAAAAAAAAAAAAAUACAAAUAAAAAGGAAAAAAAAUUACAUUUUUUAUCUUAUACCUCAGAUAUUUUGUUCUGUGUAUUUUAAUAUUGUGGGUCUUUAAUUUCUGAAGGUUCCGUAGUUUGGUUGCUGGCUGUAGGAGUUUUUGUGGUUGAUCUAGACAGAUGCUAGAUAAUGAAUAAAAACUGGUUUAGGGCCAUAUCCAGAGUGCUAUAUUAUGUAAAUGAAUUAUAUAUGCUGAAUAUUAAGCUACUGGGGUUAUCAGCUAUUUGGGAAGAGUGUAAGUGACUACAGUAGUCAUUUUUUUCUGCACCUGCAUUAUUUUAUUUUGCGAAAGGGGAGGUUGGGAGGGGCUUAGGGGAUUGGAACUGGGGUUUGGCUGAAAGAAAAAAAAAAAAAUGUAACUGAUGAAUCUAAACGACCCACUGCACCAACAAUCAUUUAUCAAUGGUUCUAAGUUACUCAUUGCCAGUUCAAGCCAAAGGUCAUGUUGUUAAGGGGGUGCUUCUAGUAGCACUUGUGCAUCUGAGUUGAAUGAAGCUGUGCAAACCCACCCUUUAAACCAUUCCACCCGGCAGUAUUCAGCUUCUUAACCAGUCGCUAUUUAGGAAAAAAAACCCACUAGUUAGGCCAUCAACAAGCAUUCUUUUUAUAUUUCUUCCAGUAUAAUAAAUUAUUGAUAUCACUGCUGACUUUUAUAUUAUGGGAGGGAAAAAAUAACAUUAAUAAAAAGGUGAUAAAAAAGCACUGUUUCUAUUUUUUUCUUUUUUUCCAAAAAAAGAAAGUAAUAAAAACUUAAAUUCUUUGUACCAGUUAAAAAAAAUGUAUAAAAUUUACAUCUGUGCAGUGGAGUUGUUAAGUUCUAGAAACAGUCUAUGAAGCUUUAGUUUUAGCCUAGUAGAACAACUGUUAGAGACAGACGUAUAAUUUUUAUGGAAUUACAUGAUAAUCAUAUUCGGAUUUAUAGAAGCAUUUUACAAGUAUUGCAAUCAUUGAGUAGAGAUAAUCAUGGUAUUUUCAUCAGCUUGGUACUUUUUGAAACGUGACUGCGUUGUGUGAACAAUCUGCAAUUUUUCAGUCCGUGAGAUCCUGCCCUUCCACCUCUUUCCCAUACCCCCAAGGAUUAUCUCAAAAUGAUCUCUUUAGUUCUGUCUCCAAGGCCCAGGACACUUGUCAGAAGGAUGCAAAAAAAGAAAAAAGUACAUCCACCCUCUUAAUCCCAAAAGAACAAAGUCUCCCCACCUUUCUCGGAUGCAGGGCCAGAGUGACACAGCCGAAAAAUUGCAGUUUGUCUGUACUUCUGUUUGAACUUUCCACGUUGUCCUGUUUACAAGUUAACUUAAGUUGGGGUAUCCGUCACGGGUCUUCCUGUUUUGUAUUUAAAUAAAAACAACAGCAGCAGGCUGUCCCUGAGUAGUUUUGCUGCCAUAGGUUAAGUCCUCAUGUGUACAGUGCAGGCCCUGUGGCCCGCACUUCAGUAAGUUAUCAACUCUCACCGCUGUGAACCUGCCAAUCCGCUGUAACAACUCUGCUUUAAAACAAAACCAAACAAAACUUUAAAAAAAAAUGUGUGAUCCAGCUUUCUCUUGCCAUCCUAUGUGCAUGCCGUAAGAUCAGUUGGAUAUUAAACCAUCAAUAAAGUUUCACAAGAUUUGAAAACAAAGUUUCUGUAGCUUCGAUACCUAAGACAGACGAUAGUGAUCUUGAAAAGAGAAAAGGGGGAGGGGGGAGCUACUUAUCAGCCAAAAGCAUAUAAAGUGUUCUUUUCACCAGACUUCUUUGGGUGGGUGAGGGGAGGGGCAAGAGGGUGUUUUAUAGCAUCACUAAGACAUUCUCAUUCCCCCACCUGGAAAACAGUGUUAUGGCAAUGGGUGCCUGGUUGAUGUUCUUAAAGGAAACGAAUUAUUAAAACACUAUGACAUCCUCCAGAGGGAAGAAAGAGUAGGAGCAGGGGGCUAUGGAGAAUAAAUUUCUCCCAAUUGCCGCCUCAGAUUUCAAAAUCCAGAAUUUGUAUUGUGUUUCGAAUCACAAACAUAGAAUUCUUACUGUGUUGGUUAAAGUAAAAUUCAUUUGCAGUUUUGAUUUUCAUCAAUGAGCUGUACUUUCCCCCAUGACUGUAUGUAGUUUUAAUAAAAUCAUUUAGAGUGAGUGAGUGCCAACCGAUGUUGCAGAAUCUUUUGUCUAGGCACUCCAAGAUGCCAAUAAGUCAUUUUAAAAUGUAUGUCAGAGAUGUAAACAAACAUUUUGGAUUUUUUUUAAACAGUAUUUAUUUGGAAUGUUUUCAUUUAUCUAAAUAACUAUUGCUAUUAUGAAUUAUGGAAAAUUAAUAUUAUGUGUGGCAUAUAGUGACUUCUUAACACACACAUCACGCAAUCUGCAAACCCAGAAAAUGUGUAUAUCUGUCUUUAGAAAUUAGUGUUUAUAUCACUUACAGUGGUUUGUGAAUAAAGAAAACUGGUUUGUAAUAUCAAAAAAAUAAAAGCUUAGUCUGAAAAGGUA